AGUUAGUGGGUAGGCCUGAGAGCCGAGGAAAACUGAGCGUGGGCCUCAGAAAGAAGUUAAGGCACCCGCGAGCCGGGCAACUGCCCUCCUUCCGCGCCGGCGGAGCGAUUAAAGUGAAGAAACAAUGGCCAGCAAUCACAAAUCUUCAGCAGCUCGCCCUGUUUCAAGAGGUGGAGUUGGGUUAACAGGAAGGCCUCCUUCUGGGAUACGACCCCUAUCAGGAAAUAUUCGAGUGGCAACUGCAAUGCCACCUGGGACAGCAAGACCAGGUUCUCGUGGUUGUCCCAUAGGGACUGGUGGAGUUCUGUCUUCUCAAAUCAAAGUUGCCCAUCGCCCUGUAACACAACAAGGUUUGACUGGAAUGAAAACUGGGACGAAAGGUCCCCAGAGGCAAAUUUUAGACAAAUCUUACUAUCUUGGGCUUCUUAGAAGUAAAAUAAGUGAACUUACAACUGAAGUUAAUAAACUUCAGAAGGGAAUAGAAAUGUACAAUCAAGAGAAUUCAGUAUAUUUGUCAUAUGAAAAGAGGGCUGAGACUUUAGCUGUUGAGAUAAAAGAGCUUCAAGGACAACUAGCAGACUACAACAUGUUGGUAGAUAAACUUAAUACCAACACUGAAAUGGAAGAAGUAAUGAAUGAUUACAAUAUGCUUAAAGCUCAAAAUGAUCGAGAAACACAAAGUUUGGAUGUCAUAUUUACUGAAAGACAAGCGAAAGAAAAACAAAUCAGAAGUGUCGAAGAAGAAAUUGAACAGGAAAAACAAGCAACAGAUGACAUUAUCAAAAAUAUGUCUUUUGAAAACCAAGUCAAGUACCUAGAGAUGAAAACCACAAAUGAGAAACUGUUACAGGAAUUAGAUACACUUCAACAACAAUUGGAUUCACAGAACAUGAAAAAAGAGAGCCUGGAAGCAGAAAUAGCUCACUCCCAGGUGAAACAGGAGGCGGUAUUGCUGCAUGAAAAACUUUAUGAGUUGGAGUCCCAUCGAGAUCAAAUGAUUGCAGAAGACAAAAGCAUAGGAUCUCCAAUGGAAGAGAGAGAGAAAUUACUUAAGCAGAUUAAAGAUGAUAAUCAGGAAAUAGCCAGCAUGGAAAGACAGUUAACAGAUACAAAAGAAAAGAUAAAUCAGUUUAUUGAAGAAAUUAGACAACUUGACAUGGAUUUAGAGGAACACCAAGGUGAAAUGAACCAGAAAUACAAGGAGCUAAAGAAAAGGGAGGAACAUAUGGACACUUUUAUUGAGACUUUUGAGGAAACAAAGAAUCAGGAACUGAAACGAAAGGCACAGAUAGAAGCCAACAUUGUUGCACUCUUGGAGCACUGCAGUCGAAAUAUAAAUCGUAUAGAACAGAUAUCCUCUAUCACCAAUCAAGAGCUAAAGAUGAUGCAGGAUGACCUCAAUUUUAAAUCUACUGAAGUGCAGAAAUCACAAAGUACAGCUCAGAAUUUGACUUCAGACAUUCAACGUCUGCAGUUGGAUCUGCAGAAAAUGGAGCUUCUAGAAAGUAAGAUGACUGAAGAACAGCAUUCUCUAAAAAGCAAAAUUAAGCAAAUGACAACUGAUCUGGAGAUAUAUAAUGAUUUGCCAGCUUUAAAAUCAUCAGGUGAAGAAAAGAUAAAGAAAUUACAUCAGGAGAGAAUGAUAUUAUCAACCCACAGAAAUGCCUUUAAGAAAAUAAUGGAGAAGCAAAACAUAGAGUAUGAGGCACUAAAAACACAAUUGCAAGAAAAUGAGACACAUUCUCAGCUUACAAAUUUGGAGAGAAAGUGGCAACACCUUGAGCAAAAUAAUUUUGCGAUGAAAGAAUGAUGUCUCUGCCUGGAGAACUAGAUCCUGACUCAGUGGCAGCAUAGGUUCUCCCCCAGGGUGGUGCUGAACUUCAGCUCAGAAGCAGCCUGGACCCCAUCUUACCUCCAGAUAAGGUGUUUUAGGUACUCUGUUGCCAGUGUUAGUGCAACUUAGUUUAAAAAUAGAGGACUUGUUCACAGUAUGCUCUAAGUCUCACACUGGAGUUUUGUGCAACAUAAAGUAGGUGAUUUUGGAGCAGAGCGAAGUCUAGAAAUUUGCCUUAAAUUAUUUGUGGUACUCUAGAGAACGUGGUAUGUGUAUGUGUGUAUGUGUGUUUGAAUAUAGGAACUAGUUCAUUGAACGUUAGAUUGUUCUAAGACCAGAAUUAGAUUAAAAAUGCAUAACAUAUUAAGUAUUAAAAAGUGUUUAUAUUGUAUAUGAAUUUUUUGCGGUAAGUUUAGCUUGGCAUUUUAGGUUUUAAUUGAUGCUUAAUCUGUUAAAAUGAUGUACUGUAUUUUAAAGUAUUCUAAUUGUGCUUUUUUGUACCAUCUUCAGUAUGAAAAAUGUCAGUAUUUAGUUCCUUUCUCAGGCACAAUUAGAUUUUUAUUGACAUUGUUUUCCCCCUUAACUCAUGUAAUUAGUCAUAGCAACCAAGAGUCAAGAGAGUGAUUACCAGCCAAUUAAGAAAAAUGUGACCAAGCAGAUUGCAGAGUACAAUAAAACCAUCGUGGAUGCUUUACAUAGCACCAGCGGAAACUGAGUUUAAGUCCACUGAAAGUCUCUAAGGAAGUAUCCUCUUGCUGCUAAACUUGGUACAAGUUGACUACCAAAAAAAAAAAAAGCUUACUUUUGGAGUUUACCUAAAAUUUCUGAAUGUUAUAAUUUUUGUGGCCUCUUUUAAGAAUGAUAUUUUAAAAUAGUAAAUAGUUCAAUAAAUGGUUUGCAUAUUAAAAAGUACCAUCUUCUUUUCUUUUUAUGCUACUUGUAUUUGAACCAAGAGAUAAAGAAACUAAAAGUGACCGUUGAAAUUUAUUUAGCUGGUAUAAUCCAUCUAUGGCAACAAAUGAGAUAAGCUUUUCUUGUAUCAACUCUAGGACGGAUGCAUGGAGUAUGAUUCUGAUUUAGCACUUAGAUCAACCUUGUCAAUUUUUACUUCUAGAAAAAAUUAGUAAGAUUAGAAGGGAGAUUUUUAGCUUUGAAUGUUACUUCUCAAAUAGGUUAUAUUUGAUGUGUAUUAGACCAUAUAAUGUCACAGGUAAAUAUAUAACAUAUAUUCUUUAUAUAGCAGUUAUACCUAAAGAUUUGGAAUUAGAAACUUUUAAUCUUUGCAAUUCUUAAAAUAUUUUUUCACAUAUAUAUACCUGGAAGAACAUUAGGUAAAAGACUACAUUUAUAGUGGGCUGUUUUGGACUAUGGCUACUGCUGUUCAUUGCCACCCUGCAGUAUGCAUUUACUCUCUUGUACUAUUAGGAGAACUUAAGUAGAUUAAUUUAUAAACAUUAGCCAGAAUAUUUGGGGAAAAAAGCUAGAAGAGGUAGGAUUGGGAGAGAGGCAUAGAGUCUGGAAGACAUUAUAUUAACUGUAGAUGUAUCUUCUCUUAUCGUGCAGGAAUGAGUCACCUUGGCCAGCAUAAAAUAUUACUUAAAACUAUCCUGUUUUUGCUCUGAUAUCAUGUUCACUAAGUAACUCUACUUUUCAGUAUUUCUGAAACAACACAUUGAUUUCUUAAACCAAAAUAGCUUUAUUGAGAUAUUAUUUACAUACUUUAAAAUUUACUCAUAUAUGUUGAUUUUUAAAAAUAAAUAUUUAUAAUGGUAAAUUAUUCAAAUUCAGUCUAUAUACAUUUAAAUAAAGGAGUGAGCAUUGUUGAGUUUGCUGAACUCUGGAUUACUAAUAUGGCUGAAGAUCCUGGACAUUCAUUAAGGUAGCAUUCAUAAAAUGUGUUCCAUAAAUCCUGAGCAUCUUGAGUUAUUAAUAGUGUUAUGCCUCCAAAGGAUUCAUGGUCAAAGAAGUUUGGGAAACGUUGUCUGAAACAAAGGUGAAUUAUUUUAUUUUUUCUUGACUGCUCAUAACCCUUAAUAUGCUAAUGUAUAAUAAGCUCAAGAAGAAUAUAUACUGUAAAGCAUUUCCCAGAGAUAGUUGUCCACAAAACCCUAACUUUCACAGAGCCUAGGUCACAUGAGAUGUGUCAUUCCAAGAAAUAGACUUUGUACACCAAAUAGACUUCAUACACUAAAAUAAUUUCAUCUACUCAAGUCCUCUGGGUGGCUCUAUGGCCUUUUUCAGAUGACUCCUGAGUAUGUCUCUUUUUAGCCACCCUCAGCUGUUUUAUGCUGUGAUUGUAUGGGGUUUUCUAUUGGAAAUUGGUAGCAGAAAGUGCUUAUAAAAUUUCACAAGGGAAAAAAACUCUUUUAGCAGUUAAAGAGAAUGAAAUCUGAAAUUCAGUAGAUAAAACAGGUAAUAGAUUUUGAUGACAGUUUGCAGCCCUUCGUUCAUUCAUAAAGUAUUACUGUAAUUUGGUGAUUAGGAGCCUUUAUGGAUAUACCCGACUGCUGAAAAACAUUCAUCUUUUAUACAGUAACAAACAGAGGUAUGAUUGAGCAUAGAGUUUAGGCAAGAGAACUGACUACUAUGGUCUCUUAAUCACAUUGAUUCUAUUUCGUGGAUACUUCCAAGGAGGAAGGGAAUCUGGAAAACAUGUUUGUGGAUAGGUAAUCUUUGUUUUCCUCAUUUGAAAGCAAAUUUAAAUGCCUUUACUUUUUCCUUAGGUUUUUUUUUAUGAUUUCUACUUAAGUGUUCUUGACAUUUUACUGCACCCUUUUAAAUAACCAACUUAGUAAUUUUUACUAUUAGUAAUAAGGGUUUUUUUCUGAGUGGUGGGAUUAUGGGUGAUUGUAAUCUUCCUUGGGCUUUUUGGUAUUUUCAAAAUUGUCUGUGAUGUACAUUUAAUACUUAGAAAUGCAAUAAAAUUCAAAUAAAGUACUAUAUGCAGUUACUACUUUAACUGACAGAAAGGAUGUAGUAAAAACUCUUAAGUCCUUGACUCUAGAACUGAACCAAUCUUUACGCAGAAAGAAAGUAGGAGGAAGAUUGGCCUGUCCAUUAAAUAUAUGUGUUUGCAUUAUAACAAUGGGAAAUUUGGCAGGAAAAAAAUUUCUUGACAAAAAGCAAGGCUUUCAAUUUCCAUCCUAAUUUAUUCAUAUGUAAUAUUGGUGGGGGGCAAAUAAUUGAGCAGGAUUUCUUUAAAUUAAAACAUGUUUUAUCUGAGGGAAAUUCUCACUAAUGUCUCUCUUCCUUCCUCUGAGAGCCUUUCCACAAAUCCAACAAGAAUAUUCUCUUUACUGGGAUAGAACUGGAGGCUAAUAGCUGCAUGAACUGGCUCUUCCUGAGUCAGUCACAUUACUCAGGGGGUUCCAUUCAUGCUAAAAUAACACCUUGUAAGUCACAUGGAAAGAAGCUGCAGACUGAACAAACAUGCUGAGCAGUUUUACUAGUGAAGAUCAACAUGGGAAAGUUAGCAAGUCUUUGUUUUUCCCAUCCUUAUCUUUUAUCAGUAAAUAAACAUGAGUUCUUGAUAUUCUUUUUCCUGUGGAGCCCCUCGUUUGGACAAUACUAUAGUCUCAUUUUAAGGUACAAAAUUCAGUGCCUGCUUAGAGGAUUACAGCAUGGAGUAAUCAUAUUCACACCAGAGAUGAAAGGCCAGUUAGUAGUAGUUCCAGGGGUUUUUGCUGUUCCCUUGCUCAGUUUCUCUAGACUUCUUUCCUUUUGCUAUACAAUUGCAGUGUAAACAACCUUAGGGAAAUUAUAAUGUUUAGACUCAAAGUAAGAAGAAAUAAAGAUGGACCACUAGAGAAUUGUAGUAAUCUAUUUUUAAAUUGAUAUUGUGUCUCAUUUUUGUAUAACUUUUGAAAUAAAAGUAGAUUAUGUCUUAAAAUUGUAAGUUUACAGUUUGAUAACUGAAAAACAUUUUUAAAAAGGCAAUUUUUAAUACAAAGGUAGAUAAUUUAGGAAGACAGAUAAAUAAAAUGAAGAAAGUAAGUUACUUGUGAUCUCACCAGUCUUUUUAGAUACGCAUCUAUAUUUAUGUCACACAUAUCUGUUUUAUUUAUGUAUUUAUGCACCUUUAAUUAAAUUAAAAUUAUAUUGUUUUUAAUUUUA